CUGCCCAGACUUGAAGCCACACAGGCAGGUCGGGCAGGCGGGUCGCAGGUUGUAAAUCCAUGUGGCGGGGGCUUUGGACCCUGGCGGCCCAAGCGGCACGUGGGCCUCGCAGAUUGUGCACGCGCCGGAGCAGCGGCGCACCAGCCCCCGGCUCCGGCGCCACCAUCUUCGCGCUAAGCUCUGGCCAAGGCCGCUGCGGCAUCGCAGUGAUCCGGACCAGCGGCCCCGCCAGCGGCCACGCCCUCCGAAUUCUCACAGCACCCCGAGACCUGCCCCUUGCUCGCCACGCCAGCCUGCGCCUGCUCAGCGAUCCCCGCUCCGGGGAGCCUCUGGACCGCGCACUGGUGCUCUGGUUCCCAGGUCCCCAGAGUUUCACCGGUGAGGACUGCGUGGAGUUCCACGUGCAUGGAGGCCCGGCAGUGGUGAGCGGCGUCCUGCAGGCCUUGGGCAGCGUGCCAGGGCUUCGACCGGCGGAGGCAGGCGAGUUCACCAGACGGGCGUUCGCCAAUGGGAAGCUGAACCUGACCGAAGUGGAGGGGCUGGCGGACCUUAUCCACGCGGAAACAGAGGCGCAGCGGCGGCAGGCCCUCAGGCAGCUGGACGGAGAGCUGGGCCACCUCUGCCGUGGCUGGGCCGAGACCCUCACCAAAGCUCUGGCCCACGUGGAGGCCUAUAUCGAUUUCGGCGAGGAUGACAACCUGGAGGAGGGGGUCCUGGAGCAAGGUGGGUCUACCUGGUGGUGGGGGAGGAAGACACCUCAUAUCAGCCCUCAAAGGCUCCCCUCACUGUCUCUCUCUGCCUGCCUUCUCUCACCCACAGCCGACAUCGAAGUACGGGCACUGCAGGUGGCCCUGGGUGCACAUCUACGAGAUGCCAGGCGCGGGCAGAGGCUCCGCUCAGGGGUGCACGUAGUGGUCACUGGACCCCCCAAUGCGGGCAAGAGCAGCCUAGUGAACCUGCUCAGUCGGAAGCCUGUGUCCAUCGUGUCCCCGGAGCCAGGGACCACCCGUGACGUGCUGGAGACCCCAGUCGACCUGGCCGGAUUUCCUGUGCUGCUGAGCGACACGGCUGGGUUGCGGGAGGGCGUGGGGCCCGUGGAGCAGGAGGGCGUGCGGCGCGCCCGGGAGAGGCUAGAGCAGGCUGACCUCAUUCUGGCCAUGCUGGAUGCUUCUGACCUGGCCUCUCCCUCCAGUUGCAACUUCCUGGCCACCGUCGUAGCCUCUGUGGGAGCCCAGAGCCCCAGUGACAGCAGCCAGCGCCUCCUCCUGGUGCUGAACAAGUCGGACCUGCUGUCCCCGGAGGGCCCAGGUCCCGGUCCUGACCUGCCCCCGCACCUGCUGCUGUCCUGUCUGACGGGAGAGGGGCUGGACGGCCUCCUGGAGGCGCUGAGGAAGGAGCUAGCUGCAGUGUGUGGGGACCCGUCCACAGAUCCCCCGCUGCUGACCCGAGCAAGGCACCAGCACCACCUCCAGGGUUGCCUGGAUGCCCUCGGCCACUACAAGCAGUCAAAAGACCUGGCCCUGGCGGCAGAGGCGCUGCGGGUGGCCCGGGGUCACCUGACCCGGCUCACAGGUGGAGGGGGUACCGAGGAGAUCCUGGACAUCAUCUUCCAGGACUUCUGUGUGGGCAAGUGACGGGAUCCAGGGAAGUCGCACCCAAGCUGCGUGGAGACCCAGGAGCCUCGGGGGAUCUGGAAACAGUUUAGGCCAAUUGGGAUUCUCAUUCGCCUGGGAAAGAACUUGAUUCUCAAAUAGUGAAGCAACACAGCUGAGAGGUAGUGAGAUCCCUGCAGGGACUCCCUGGAGAUUCAGGCCCUGGAAUGGGGCUGAAUGGAGGUCCCGUUCGACCCUUGAUGCUGGGGCAUCCGGGUUGGGAUGGAGAUAGGAGGAUCUCAGUAUAUUUGUUUCGUAGUUUUUUAUUUAUUUUGCAAAUACCAAAGGAAUGUAAAAAAAACUCAGGUGAUCUAGAAGUGUUUAUUUUCUUCCCUUCCCUUCCCUUCCCUUUCCUUUUCCCUUUCCCUUUCCCCUUCCCCUUCCCCUUCCCCUUCCCCUACCCUUCCCUCCUCUGUCUAUUGCCCAGGCUGGAGUGCAGUGGUGCGACCUUGGCUCACUGCAACCUCCAUCUCCGGGGCUCAAGCGCUUCUCCUGCCUCAGCCUCCUGAGUAGCUGGGAUUACAGGCAUGUGCCAGCAUGCCCGGCUAAUUUUUUUCUUUUUUUGAGACAGAGUCUCGCUCUGUCACCCAGGCUGGAGUUCAGUGGUGCGACCUCGGCUUACUGCAACCUCCACCUCCCGGGUUCAAGUGAUUCUCCUGCCUCAGCCUCUUGAGUAGCUGGGACUACAGGCGCACACCACCACGCCAGGCUAAUUUUUGUAUUUUUAGUAGAGACAAGGUUUCACCAUGUUGACCAGGCUGGUCUUGAACUCCUUGACCUCAGGUAAUCUGCCUACCUUGGCCUCCCAAAGUGCUGGGAUCACAGGCGUGAGCUAUCACACCUGGCCCCAGAAGUGUUUCAACAUGGAAAUUUUCCUUAGCCCUUCUGUGGUUGUCAUGGCUUAAUGUGUGUCUUUCCAGAACUUUGAAUGUUUGCAUACUUGUGGAUGUACCUUUCAAAUAUGUUUGUCUUGUGUAUCAUAUAUAAAUGGUAUUGUGUUCAUUGCUCUA